GGUAAGCAUGCUUGGAAUAUUUAAGGAUCCAGACGGAUUCCACGGGGGUGCAGCCAAGUGGGCUGUGGGAGGAGAAGGACAUAAGGUCAGUGAUGCACCAGGGGCACACCUGUCGUCUUGCAGGACUUGGUACUGAAACAGCCUUCAUUACUUAGAGACCAUAGCUUUUUUGCAAGUUACUAUUCCCUGCAUUUAGAAAGUUCAUCUUUAAACAGGCAAUUCAGUAAGUAAAUAUUCUAUGGCUCUAAAACAGAUACGGCUGUUGGAGACUUUAAAACAUCUGACAGUUACAUUUUUAAUGUUGUCUACCAAGGCUAUUACAUUUCCUCUGUCAAAGUAACUUAAUUUUAAAAACGAACUCUGUGCUUGUUAAACGAAAAGGCCAGAAGGCUACUGGCUACUCAGCGUUCAUUUGAAAUUCUUAUAGUGCCUUCAGUACAAUUCAAACUUAGAGGUGAUUCUCACAAUUCAUGUGAAGCAACAUUUUACAAAAAAAAUCACCUACGUUCACUGUUAAGUCAGAAGACAGAAUGAUUAACAAAAUCUCAGCCGCGAAUUACUCUCACGAUGGCCAACUGGAUAUUAAAUAACUCUGCAUUAUUUUAAUGGAAUGUUAUAAAGGAUUUGCAACAAAAUGCAGACGUAGAUUUAGGGACUGCCGACUUCUAUAGAUCAAGGACUUCAUUGGUGCAGCUGAGGAAAUUCUUCCAAACAAGUCUAAAUGUUGGAAAUCCACCAAACUGCAGAGAAAGACCUCUUGCCUCCGUAUUCUUUCUUCAUCUGUAAAAAUGUUGACUUCUGCUUUUCAGACUACGCGCACAGCCUCUUUAUUUCCUACUGCGGCUUCAUUCCCUCACGGAACACUGACGCCAUCGCGAAGGAAGCAUUUCGAGCACGACUGACGCUCCCCUUAUUAUUUGCUAAGCCGCUGCGCUCGGGUCUGGCUACGAUUUGCUUUCAGAAUAACGGGAAGGUGCAACAAGAUCGCUUCCCUAGAGGCGCGUCGCCCGCGUGGCCCGGACCCCCCACGCCCGCCCGCCGCCCCGUGGGUGCGCACGCGUGUCCGCGCAGGCUUCCCGCCUGGCGAGUGCAAGGCUCCUCUCCGCCGUGCUGCUUUCCAGCCUCUCAGCAAAUCACGAACACCGAAAGAAGCCACGGCGGCGACGGGAGGGGCGUCGCGCGUGCUUCCCUCGGCGACAAAGCGGGAGCCGGGCGCGCCGGCCGAGGGCGCCCGGCGCAGAGUCCCGCAGAGGCGGACGCCGCGGCACGCGCCUCGAAAAGCCUCAAACUCUUAUCCUCGGCUCUCCCGCCCCACCUCCGCCCCGCAGCCAAGACCCGCGCCGUGGCGGGCCCGACGGCCAAGGAAAGCCCACCAGCCCUCCGCACCGUGGGCGACGGGCCAAGACCCGGCCCUAAACGGCCAGACCCAGCCCCUAGUCGGCUGCCGCCCCCGCCCCACGCAGGCGCGCUCCGGGGCCCUCCCCUCCCCCACCGCGCGCUCGCGGGGCCCGACGGGGGCGGAGCGACCCUCGGAAGGGGCGUGGCGACCGGGCUCGACGCGCGCACGCGCUCUGGAGCCCCACGGCUACGUGUCGGGCCACCCCCGACCGCGCCCGCAGCCCCACCCGCCCCGUGCCGUGGAAAGCCCCGCGCCCCCCCCGCGGCCGUCGGCCCCGCAGCCCACACCCACCCGCCCCGGGCGCCCCGCACGGCGGCGACCCAGUCCUUGCGCCCAGGCCCGCCGAGCGCCGCAGUCCGUCACACUCCCGUUGCCCCCGUCGCCCGCCCCGCCGGGGAGGCAGGGAGGAGGGGGCGCGGCGCCGGCGGCUGCCCCGGUCGCGGGGCGGCGGGCAGCAGGCAGCGGGAGCGCGCCGGCCGGGACCCGCUAACGGCCGCCCUGCGCGGCCCCGCCCGCCGCCCGCCCCCGGCCCUCCCCGCGCCGCUGCCCCUCCCCCCGCCGCCGCCGCUGCUGCCGCCGCCGCUGGCAGCGCCGCCUGAACUGAGGCGAACUCCGCCGCCAACGGCGGCGGCUGGGAGCGCGUCGGGCCCGGGCGGAAAGUGCCUGCGGGGGGCGGGCGAGCGCGCGGUGCCGGCCGCCCCGGGGCUCGGCGCGGGAGCCAGAGCGGGAGCCGGCGCGGAGCGGGACGCCGGGUCCCGAGCGGCCCGCGGCCGGGGCUCGCCCCCGCCCCUCCCUCCUCUCCGGCGGCGGCGGCGGCGGCGGCGGGCGGAGUGA